AACCAGGGGCGGAGGCGGCGGCCAGGGAGGAAGCGGAGGAGGCGGAGGCGGCCGCGGCGUUCGCCCGCCCGCUCGCUCGCUCGGUUUCCCCGCCCCCGCCGGGCUUAACGCCGCUGAAGGUAUCCGGGUGCGCGCUGUCGCAACCUGCCCUCAUCCUGGCCCGCGACUGUAAGACCGGACCCACAUCCAGACCAAUCUUCCUGUCCGGGCUGCUGCGACGCGGGCUCCGCAGGUUGCAGGCGGGCGGCCGGGGCGCCUGAAGGUUACCGAGUGCAUGAGCGCCUAGCGCUUCCCGCGCUGCCCCGCCCGCUGGCCCGCCGACCCGCCCGCCGGCUCGCCCGCCAGCCCCUCGGCGCCCGGCGGCGGCGGCGGCGGUGGCGGCGACGGUCGCAGGAGGUGCCGUCUGCCUCCCAGGUGCGCGCUUCGCUCCCGGAGCCGCGGAACUCGGCGGCCGCCAUGGCGUCCAACAUGGACCGGGAGAUGAUCCUGGCGGAUUUUCAGACUUGAAUUGCUUGGUUGGUGUCCUUUCUCCAGGAAUACUUUAAAGGAUAAGUAAAGGCUGUUCUCUUAAUAAACCCAGUCGUAGUGCCACUGACAUGCAUGUACUGGCAUUGAAAACAUUGACGAAGCUAUUACAUUGCUUGAACAAAAUAAUUGGGACUUAGUGGCAGCUAUCAAUGGUGUAAUACCACAGGAAAAUGGCAUUCUACAAAGUGAAUAUGGAGGUGAGACCAUACCAGGACCUGCAUUUAAUCCAGCAAGUCAUCCAGCUUCAGCUCCUACUUCCUCUUCUUCUUCAGCGUUUCGACCUGUAAUGCCAUCCAGGCAGAUUGUAGAAAGGCAACCUCGGAUGCUGGACUUCAGGGUUGAAUACAGAGACAGAAAUGUUGAUGUGGUACUUGAAGACACCUGUACUGUUGGAGAGAUUAAACAGAUUCUAGAAAAUGAACUUCAGAUACCUGUGUCCAAAAUGCUGUUAAAAGGCUGGAAGACGGGAGAUGUGGAAGACAGUACGGUCCUAAAAUCUCUACACUUGCCAAAAAACAACAGUCUUUAUGUCCUUACACCAGAUUUGCCACCACCUUCAUCAUCUAGUCAUGCUGGUGCCCUGCAGGAGUCAUUAAAUCAAAACUUCAUGCUGAUCAUCACCCACCGAGAAGUCCAGCGGGAGUACAACCUGAACUUCUCAGGAAGCAGUACUAUUCAAGAGGUAAAGAGAAAUGUGUAUGACCUUACAAGUAUCCCCGUUCGCCACCAAUUAUGGGAGGGCUGGCCAACUUCUGCUACAGACGACUCAAUGUGUCUUGCUGAAUCAGGGCUCUCUUAUCCCUGCCAUCGACUUACAGUGGGAAGAAGAUCUUCACCUGCACAGACCCGGGAACAGUCGGAAGAACAAAUCACCGAUGUUCAUAUGGUUAGUGAUAGCGAUGGAGAUGACUUUGAAGAUGCUACAGAAUUUGGGGUGGAUGAUGGAGAAGUAUUUGGCAUGGCGUCAUCUGCCUUGAGAAAAUCUCCAAUGAUGCCAGAAAACGCAGAAAAUGAAGGAGAUGCCUUAUUACAAUUUACAGCAGAGUUUUCUUCAAGAUAUGGUGAUUGCCAUCCUGUAUUUUUUAUUGGCUCAUUAGAAGCUGCUUUUCAAGAGGCCUUCUAUGUGAAAGCCCGAGAUAGAAAGCUUCUUGCUAUCUACCUCCACCAUGAUGAAAGUGUGUUAACCAACGUGUUCUGCUCACAAAUGCUUUGUGCUGAAUCCAUUGUUUCUUAUCUGAGUCAAAAUUUUAUAACCUGGGCUUGGGAUCUGACAAAGGACUCCAACAGAGCAAGAUUUCUCACUAUGUGCAAUAGACACUUUGGCAGUGUUGUGGCACAAACCAUUCGGACUCAAAAAACGGAUCAGUUUCCGCUUUUCCUGAUUAUUAUGGGAAAGCGAUCAUCUAAUGAAGUGUUGAAUGUGAUACAAGGGAACACAACAGUAGAUGAGUUAAUGAUGAGACUCAUGGCUGCAAUGGAGAUCUUCACAGCCCAACAACAGGAAGAUAUAAAGGACGAGGAUGAACGUGAAGCCAGAGAAAAUGUGAAGAGAGAGCAAGAUGAGGCCUAUCGCCUUUCACUUGAGGCUGACAGAGCAAAGAGGGAAGCUCACGAGAGAGAGAUGGCAGAACAGUUUCGUUUGGAGCAGAUUCGCAAAGAACAAGAAGAGGAACGUGAGGCCAUCCGGCUGUCCUUAGAGCAAGCCCUGCCUCCUGAGCCAAAGGAAGAAAAUGCUGAGCCUGUGAGCAAACUGCGGAUCCGGACCCCCAGUGGCGAGUUCUUGGAGCGGCGUUUCCUGGCCAGCAACAAGCUCCAGAUUGUCUUUGAUUUUGUAGCUUCCAAAGGAUUUCCAUGGGAUGAGUACAAGUUACUGAGCACCUUUCCUAGGAGAGACGUAACUCAACUGGACCCAAAUAAAUCAUUAUUGGAGGUAAAGUUGUUCCCUCAAGAAACCCUUUUCCUUGAAGCAAAAGAGUAAACACGGCCCAGCGGUGGAACCAGCCAUUCCUUGACAAGCCAGCAGCCUGCGUCAGGAGAAGGGCUCCUCGCCAACCCACCCACACGCUCGUCUCACUCAAUUCAAUGUCACACUUCUGCCUCUUGCAAAAUUGCUGGAAAAAGUAAUAAUAAAUAUAGCUACUUAAGAUUUCCCAUCCAUGAGUAUAUAUUCCCAACCCUUAUUACAGAGAAUUACAACUCUGCCACCCUCCCCUACCCCCUGCACUUCACCCUCCUUCAAUGACGAAUGCAUUGUUCAAGUGUGAGUGAUCACUAAAUAGAAUUUUUACCUCUCCAGUGCCCAUCUUUUCCCCACAGUGUCUAGGACAGUUCUGUCUGUUCUGUGACACCAGGAUGCUGUAUAUUUGAUAUAUGUCUUUUUAUUUUCAUGACUGAAUUUCUACUUCAUCACCUAAUUUUAAGGGGCAGAGGGAAAAAAAGUCAAAUGAGACAUUGUCGGCAUGGAGAUUAAACAUUGUAGGAAAAAAGUAUACCAUUUUUGUUAGAACUUUCUGAUGGCUUUACUAAGAUGUCAGGUUUUGUUUGAGGACUGAAUUUGACAUAUAUGCAAGAUAUUUAUUUACUGCUGCUGCCUUGGGUCUCCAGGUUCUACCUAGGAGGUAUUUGCUGUUCCAUUGCAGCAUAGGGAAACUGUUCAAGCACACAAUGUGAAUGUUGAGAUCAUGUGCAGAGAGGCCAGUACCAAAACUUCAGUAUCUGGCCCAAUGGCAAGAGGCUACUGUUAGGUUUGCAUUUGGGCAGUUAGAACCUCACAGAUACCAGCUCCCAAGUUGCUAGUCCAUCAGUGUAAACUGAACACAAUUCUCUCUUGCUUUCUCUCUCUCUACUCCCUCACACAUUUGGACCUUGUCACUUGGUGUUUAAGCACCUUGCCUAUCAACAAAAUCUGAUGAGCAGCCCCAUGGACUCUCCUGUAAUAAGGAACUUGCUCUACUAUUUUAUUCUUUUAAUGUUUUAGUAUUUGAUAUUGGACUCAAAUGAAAGGGAUCUCAUUCUGUGGCUGAAAAAUCAGACUUCAUAUGUUGAAGAGAGCAAACUUGGGGACUCAACUCAGAAGACAUGUGUUGCCUGAAACCUGCAUAUAAUAAUUUUUGAUUUGAUUUAGUAAGUGUGGAUUUUUCUUAAUCUACAGAUUUGGGGUUUGGGGUUUAGAUCAUGAGAACACCGUUUAUACCUUCACAGCCAAUGAUUUAUUUUUAGUCUUGAAAUAUUUCUCCAUAUCUGUUUUUGUGUCACCUGUGGGUUUUAUCCUAGGGGUUGGGAUCCUGAUUUUAACAUUUUGUACUUGUCCAAAAAAGAGUUCAAAUGCUGGGUUUGUUCCCCCAGCCUCGGCCAAGGGGUUCUCAGAAGAUUCUAACCAAAGCUGGAGAUAGGUCUGCUCAUUUUCCUUCUGCCCAGAAGUGGAUGUUGGCCAGGAAAAUUACACCUUGUGUCUUCUCUGAUGCUCCAACCAGGGACCUCUCCAGAUUACUAUCUAGCACAGACUAGUGCUACAUCUGCCUAGGUAUGGGCUUUCUCUGGCAGCAGGGGUCUCUCUAGGGAGGCUGAGAGACCCAUGGGUCUCCCUUCAGGGGAAGUGUUCAGGGGAGUUCAAACUGAACACUUCUCUCCAGCUCUAUUCCUAUCUUCCUAAUCUAAUGGCUCUACAAGAUAGUCAUUUCCAGUGCUACAGAUGCACCAGGGCACCACCUCUUUUUUUUUCUAGGUAGACCUUGUUCUGUAGCUGCUGUGAAGAAGCUGCAGCCCUGAACUCAGGUCAUACUCAGGAACAGCAGCAGGGGUGUGGGUGGGGUUUGAGGGAAGGUACUCUGAAUUCACCUUCAUGUUUAACCUGUUCCAUCUGACUUGGGUUUCUUCAUUAUAUUGUUCCCUCCCACUCACCUUCACUUCUGUAUUACAACAAUAUAGACUUUACUCUAAAGCCAAUUUCAUGGAAGUUAUUAAAUGCUACUUGAAUGUGUGUGAAGUUGAUACAACCUUUUUCAACCUGCCUUAGAAAGUUCUUUUGGCCUACUCAGCCCCAUGAUUUCCUAUGCUCUAGGCCUCAUAACUGGGAAAGGCCUCAGCUAAUUGUCACUGUUCACUCAGGACAUGAUGGUCUACUAAGCUUCAGACAAAAGGCCAAAGCAAUUUUAUCCUUUUCAUACAAGCAGAGCAUUAAAAUGACUUCCCAUCACCACAGAAAUAGCAGUGUCCUCUGCAGUUCUUCCUCCUACCAUUAGGCUUCCUUGGGCUUUACAUCCCAGCCUCCAGGCCCAGUAAGUGAGUCAGUCUGAAUAUUUGCUUGGCAUUCUUAUGCCCAACUGUUGACAGUGAAGCUCCAGGACUCUUUGUCAUCCCCCAUUCCAGUUUACUCCCUUGUGUUCUUGGACUGCUGGAUGUGCAGUUGCAGCAUUAGUUUGAAAGUUAAAGGAAGUGUUGCCAAUUUCCCAUUGCCUUUAAGAAGGUGCAGGGAUUUUUUUGGAGGUUUCUGAUUUCGGAUGUUGCCAUUCUCUGGCACUACUAGUUUUAUAGCACACACAGAUGUUCAUCUCUGGAUUGUAAGCAUCCAGAAUCAAAGAUGAAUGAGAGCAUCUUUUAUGGAAUCUACCUUUUUAACAUAAGAGAGUAAGAUUUAUGCUUUUAUAGAUUUUACUUGCUGCUGACAUUAGAAACAUAUUAGUCACAUAAUAACAUCUAAGUGUGCUGGUCAGUAGAAUAGGUUUUUAAGAGGUGGAGAGCUCUGGCAAAUUUCCCCCAAAGUAUAGACUUUUUCAUUUGAAUGUGGGAGAGGGUCUUAAUUCUCUCCACAACAGCAUCACUGAUUGACACAUUUCUACCCAUCCUUUUCUGUCCCUUAGCCAUCCAGUCCUGGGUCCCCACAAGUGGAUGGGACUUGGAGUCUUUAGUUCAGUCCAGGAGUAACUCAUAUAGGCAUUGCACAUUAUAGUCUGUGUAACCCUUUCACCUGUAUUUUCUCUUUUGAUCCUUUUUAAAAUUCUUAGAGGAAGAGAGAUCUUCACAUACAUAUAACCACAGCCACAUACACACACAUUCCAGAGACUUCAGUGUCUUCCAAGUUGAACCUCUCUUCUGCCACUUAGUAGCUGCGUGACCUUAAGGUAAGUAACCUCUCUGAACCUCAGUGUCCUUACAACAUUCUGAUAGCACUUUGCAAUUGGACACACCUUUCACACAUCAUAAUAGUCUCCCGCUAUGAGGGAAGCAGGGCAGAGAUGAUGAUUCCAUUUUUGCACAAGGGGCUUAGAGGAUAGUGGCUUGCCUAAAAUCACACAGCAUGUCAGUAGAAGGGUCAGGACUUAAAGUGCUAACUCUAAUUUUCCACUGCUUGUCUACAAAGAAUCUCUAAUUUUUUUUUUUUUUUUUUUUUUUUUUUGAGACAGAGUCUCGCUCUGUCGCUCAGGCUAGAGUGCAGUGGCACGAUCUCGGCUCACUGCAACCUCCAUCUCCUGGGCUCAAGCAGUUCUCCUGCCUCAGCCUCUCAAGUAGCUGGGAUUACAGGCAUGUGCCACCAUGCCCAGCUAAUUUUUGUAUUUUUAGUAGAGACAGGGUUUCACCAUGUUGGCCAGGCUGGUCUAGAACUCCUGACCUCAGGUAAUCGGCCCACCUCAGCCUCCCAAAGUGCCAGGGUUACAGGCGUGAGCCACGGCGCCCGGCCAAGAAUCUCUAAAUUUUAUAUUCAAGAACGGAUCUUGGAAUCCUCUACAGUUGUACAUAAAAAGUUAAACAUCACUUUGGGAGGCAAAGGCAGGAGGAUUGCUUGAGGCCAGAAGUUCAAGACCAGCCCUGACCACAUACCAAGACCCUGUCUCUAAAAAAAUAAAUAAAUAAAAAAUAAAACUUUUCAUUAGCCAGGCAUGCUGGUACUUGCCUGUAGUCCCAGCUACUGUUGAGGCUGAGGCAAAGUGAUCACUUGAGCCCAGGAGUUCAAGGCUACAGUGAGCCAUGAUAGUGCGACUGCUACUCUGGCCUAGGCAUCAGAGUAAGACCUCAUCUCUUUAAAAAAAAAAAAAAAAGAAAGGUUAAACAUGUAUUUUCCUGGAAAGGGAAUCUGUAUUCAUCAGAUUCUCAGUGGGACCUAUUGAUCAAAAAAUUUUAAGAAUCACCAUUUACGUCAUCCUAUUUGGGGAGAAGAAUCUGUCCAUUCUUUUUAUCAAUCCGUAUUUUUAUCUAAAAGAAACCUCCAGAGGAUGAAAUACAAUCACUAGACUUUCUUGCCUUGAAUAUCUCUGCAUUUAGUAUUUUGUCCUUGUCUCAAAUAAUCUGCUUUGGAAGGUGACACUUAACCCCAACUGGCCACACAGCUCCUCACUGUUGCAUUUUGAAAGUUUGGUCUGAAAGAAAAUAUUAAUAAAAGAGACAUGAUCUCCA